CUAGAGGGCUUCGCCAACUGUGUGGGGCUGGCGGCCGGCGGGAGAGGCGGCCGGCCUGGACUGGCCCGAGAGGGAUCCCGGUUCCCAGAACAGACCUAGGAGGCGGCCUCGAGGGCGGACGGCAGGGAGGGCCAGCAUGCCCCGACUGCUGCACCCCGCCCUGCCGCUGCUCCUGGGCGCCACGCUGACCUUCCGGGCGCUCCGGCGCGCGCUCUGUCGCCUGCCCCUACCCGUGCACGUGCGCGCCGACCCCCUGCGCACCUGGCGCUGGCACAACCUGCUCGUCUCCUUCGCUCACUCCAUUGUGUCGGGGAUCUGGGCACUGCUGUGUGUAUGGCAGACUCCUGACAUGUUAGUGGAGAUUGAGACGGCGUGGUCACUUUCUGGCUAUUUGCUCGUUUGCUUCUCUGCGGGGUAUUUCAUCCACGAUACGGUGGACAUCGUGGCUAGCGGACAGACGCGAGCCUCUUGGGAAUACCUUGUCCAUCACGUCAUGGCCAUGGGUGCCUUCUUCUCCGGCAUCUUUUGGAGCAGCUUUGUCGGUGGGGGUGUCUUAACACUACUGGUGGAAGUCAGCAACAUCUUCCUCACCAUUCGCAUGAUGAUGAAAAUCAGUAAUGCCCAGGAUCAUCUCCUCUACCGGGUUAACAAGUAUGUGAACCUGGUCAUGUACUUUCUCUUCCGCCUGGCCCCUCAGGCCUACCUCACCCAUUUCUUCUUGCGUUAUGUGAACCAGAGGACCCUGGGCACCUUCCUGCUGGGUAUCCUGCUCAUGCUGGACGUGAUGAUCAUAAUCUACUUUUCCCGCCUCCUCCGCUCUGACUUCUGCCCUGAGCAUGUCCCCAAGAAGCAACACAAAGACAAGUUCUUGACUGAGUGAGGGGCACAGAGCCUGGGACAACAAAAACGGACAAGGCCAGAAACAGCUUCAUAUGGACACUGGGACUUAGCCCCAAGCCUGGGUGUCCUCUGAGGCCAGCCUCUCCACCUUCUGAGCCUGCGCCCACACUAUUGAAAACACUAAUGAAAGUACUCCUCUGAA